AUGCCAGGCCCUGGGAAUACAGCAGCACUGACGGCAUUCCCAGACUGCCCUCCAGGAACUUCUACUCUCCACAUCCAGAAAUCUGGAAUCAUCACAAAUUCCUUGCCACCUCCGUUAUCCAGUCUGCCUUUGAGAACUUUCCAUCAUCAUACAGCGAGAGGCCGUGGCCACCACCUCCCAUCUCUAGUCACAGACUCCUUAUGGCAGCCCCUUGGUCCAGAAAUGGAAAGGAGAAGAGAGCGCGGGCGCAGUGGGGCAAAGUCGCCUGGGAGGCCCGAGCAGGCGACCUGGCCGCCAUCUUGGGAGAGGGCAACGCCGGCAGCUUCCAGCAAUGUGUACGGGCUGGCAGGCGGCGCCGGCGGGCGCGGGGAGCUGCUGGCCGCCACCCUUAAAGGCAAGGUGCUCGGCUUCCGCUACCAAGACCUCCGACAGAAAAUCCGGCCAGUGGCCAAGGAGCUGCAGUUCAACUACAUUCCCGUGGAUGCGGAGAUUGUCUCCAUCGACACUUUCAACAAGUCACCCCCCAAGCGGGGUCUGGUUGUGGGGAUCACGUUCAUCAAGGAUUCAGGGGACAAGGGCAGCCCCUUCCUGAACAUUUACUGCGACUACGAGCCCGGCUCUGAGUACAACCUUGACUCUAUUGCCCAGAGCUGCCUGAACCUGGAGCUCCAGUUCACUCCGUUCCAGCUGUGCCAUGCGGAGGUCCAGGUCGGGGAUCAACUUGAGACUGUGUUUCUCUUGAGUGGGAACGACCCGGCCAUUCAUCUCUACAAGGAGAACGAGGGGCUGCAUCAGUUUGAGGAACAGCCCGUGGAAAACCUCUUCCCAGAGCUGACGAACCUGACCAGUAGCGUCCUCUGGCUGGACGUCCACAACUUCCCCGGCACGUCCCGGCGCCUCUCAGCUCUGGGCUGUCAGAGUGGUUAUGUCCGUGUCGCCCACGUGGACCAGCGGAGUCGAGAGGUUCUGCAGAUGUGGUCGGUCCUGCAGGACGGUCCCAUCUCCCGAGUGAUUGUGUUCAGCCUCUCGGCCGCCAAGGAGACCAAGGACAGGCCACUACAAGAUGAGUACAGCGUGCUCGUGGCCAGCAUGUUGGAGCCAGCAGUGGUGUAUCGGGACCUGCUGAACCGGGGUCUUGAAGACCAGCUUCUCCUGCCCGGCAGUGACCAGUUUGACAGCGUCCUCUGCAGCCUGGUCACCGAUGUGGAUUUGGAUGGGCGGCCAGAAGUCCUGGUGGCCACCUAUGGACAGGAACUGCUGUGUUAUAAGUACCGGGGCCCAGAGUCGGGGCUUCCUGAGGCCCAGCACGGGUUCCAUCUGCUGUGGCAGCGGAGCUUCUCCAGUCCCCUGCUGGCCAUGGCUCACGUGGACCUGACCGGGGAUGGGCUGCAGGAGCUUGCCGUGGUCUCCCUGAAGGGCGUGCACAUCCUGCAGGUUCAAACAAUUCUCAUGCCUCAGCCUCUCAAGCAGCUGGGAAAUACAGCCGCACGCCACCACGCCCAGCUAAUUUUUGUAUUUUUAGUAGAGACGGAGUUUCACCAUGUUGCCCAGCACAGCCUGAUUCAGGCCUCAGAGCUGGUCUUGACCCGGCUUCGACAUCAAGUGGAGCAGAGGAGACGUCGGCUACAGGGGUUGGAGGACGGGGCAGGUGCAGGGCCUGCUGAGAAUGCAGCCUCUUAAGCACCCAUGCACCCACUCUUCCCAGACCUGGGGCGACUCAUGGCGUGCUCACCUCCAGCCGCUGGUGGGGGGUGUCCUGAAGGACAGGAUGCUCUCCCCAGACCUCCCCAGGGUGGUGAAGCUGUGCCCUGGGGCCCCAGCUAACCCACUCCUCUCUCUGUACGUCAAUGUCCCUAUUUGAAAGCAGGGAUGAUCCCAUUCCACCCUGUCCACUCUGGAUGAGAAUUGGCCACCUGAUGGUUAUUUAUACGUCCAGAAGAACAUCA